GUUCCUGAGGCUGGCAUCUGGAUGAGGAAACUGAAGUUGAGGAAUAGUGAAGAGUUUGUCCAAUGUCAUAGCCCCGUAAUCAACGGGACAAAAAUUUUCUUGCUGAUGGGUCAAGAUGGCAUCGUGAAGUGGUUGUUCACCGUAAACUGUAAUACAAUCCUGUUUAUGGAUUUGUUUGCAUAUUUUUCCCUCCAUAGGGAAACCUUUCUUCCAUGGCUCAGGACACACUCCUGGAUCGAGCCAACAGGAGAACUUUCUGGUAAGCAUUUGGCUAACUUUUUUUUUUUUGAGAUGGAGUCUUGCUGUGUCGCCUAGGCUGGAGUGCAGUGGCGUGAUCUUGGCUCACUGCAGCCUCCACUUCCCGGGUUCAAUCAAUUCUCCUACCUCAACUUCCUGAGUAGCUGGGAUUACAGGCGCCCGCCACCACACCCGGCUCAUUUUUGUACUUUUAGUAGAGACACAGUUUUGCCAUGUUGGCCAGGCUGGUCUUGAAUUCCUCAGCUCAGGUGAUCUGCCUGCCUUGGCCUCUCAAAGUGCUGGGAUUACAGGCGUGAGCCACUGUGCCCGGCCUUGGCUAACUUUUCAAAAUUAAAGAUUUUGACUUGUUACAGUCAUGUGACAUUUUUUUCUUUCUGUUUGCUGAGUUUUUGAUAAUUUAUAUCUCUCAAAGUGGAGACUUUAAAAAAGACUCAUCCGUGUGCCGUGUUCACUGCCUGGUAUCUUAGUGUGGACCGAAGCCUAAGGACCCUGAAAACAGCUGCAGAUGAAGAUGGCAAGCACCCGCUGCAAGCUGGCCAGGUACCUGGAGGACCUGGAGGAUGUGGACUUGAAGAAAUUUAAGAUGCACUUAGAGGACUAUCCUCCCCAGAAGGGCUGCAUCCCCCUCCCGAGGGGUCAGACAGAGAAGGCAGACCAUGUGGAUCUAGCCACGCUAAUGAUCGACUUCAAUGGGGAGGAGAAGGCGUGGGCCAUGGCCGUGUGGAUCUUCGCUGCGAUCAACAGGAGAGACCUUUAUGAGAAAGCAAAAAGAGAUGAGCCGAAGUGGGGUUCAGAUAAUGCACGUGUUUCGAAUCCCACUGUGAUAUGCCAGGAAGACAGCAUUGAAGAGGAGUGGAUGGGUUUACUGGAGUACCUUUCGAGAAUCUCUAUUUGUAAAAUGAAGAAAGAUUACCGUAAGAAGUACAGAAAGUACGUGAGAAGCAGAUUCCAGUGCAUUGAAGACAGGAAUGCCCGUCUGGGUGAGAGUGUGAGCCUCAACAAACGCUACACACGACUGCGUCUCAUCAAGGAGCACCGGAGCCAGCAGGAGAGGGAGCAGGAGCUUCUGGCCAUCGGCAAGACCAAGACGUGUGAGAGCCCCGUGAGUCCCAUUAAGAUGGAGUUGCUGUUUGACCCCGAUGAUGAGCAUUCUGAGCCUGUGCACACCGUGGUGUUCCAGGGGGCGGCAGGGAUUGGGAAAACAAUCCUGGCCAGGAAGAUGAUGUUGGACUGGGCGUCGGGGACACUCUACCAAGACAGGUUUGACUAUCUGUUCUAUAUCCACUGUCGAGAGGUGAGCCUUGUGACACAGAGGAGCCUGGGGGACCUGAUCAUGAGCUGCUGCCCCGACCCAAACCCACCCAUCCACAAGAUCGUGAGAAAACCCUCCAGAAUCCUCUUCCUCAUGGACGGCUUCGAUGAGCUGCAAGGUGCCUUUGACGAGCACAUAGGACCGCUCUGCACUGACUGGCAGAAGGCCGAGCGGGGAGACAUUCUCCUGAGCAGCCUCAUCAGAAAGAAGCUGCUUCCCGAGGCCUCUCUGCUCAUCACCACGAGACCUGUGGCCCUGGAGAAACUGCAGCACUUGCUGGACCAUCCUCGGCAUGUGGAGAUCCUGGGUUUCUCCGAGGCCAAAAGGAAAGAGUACUUCUUCAAGUACUUCUCUGAUGAGGCCCAAGCCAGGGCAGCCUUCAGUCUGAUUCAGGAGAACGAGGUCCUCUUCACCAUGUGCUUCAUCCCCCUGGUCUGCUGGAUCGUGUGCACUGGACUGAAACAGCAGAUGGAGAGUGGCAAGAGCCUUGCCCAGACAUCCAAGACCACCACCGCGGUGUACGUCUUCUUCCUUUCCAGUUUGCUGCAGCCCCGGGGAGGGAGCCAGGAGCACGGCCUCUGCGCCCACCUCUGGGGGCUCUGCUCUUUGGCUGCAGAUGGAAUCUGGAACCAGAAAAUCCUGUUUGAGGAGUCCGACCUCAGGAAUCAUGGACUGCAGAAGGCGGAUGUGUCUGCUUUCCUGAGGAUGAACCUGUUCCAAAAGGAAGUGGACUGCGAGAAGUUCUACAGCUUCAUCCACAUGACUUUCCAGGAGUUCUUUGCCGCCAUGUACUACCUGCUGGAAGAGGAAAAGGAAGGAAGGACGAACGUUCCAGGGAGUCGUUUGAAGCUUCCCAGCCGAGACGUGACAGUCCUUCUGGAAAACUAUGGCAAAUUCGAAAAGGGGUAUUUGAUUUUUGUUGUACGUUUCCUCUUUGGCCUGGUAAACCAGGAGAGGACCUCCUACUUGGAGAAGAAAUUAAGUUGCAAGAUCUCUCAGCAAAUCAGGCUGGAGCUGCUGAAAUGGAUUGAAGUGAAAGCCAAAGCUAAAAAGCUGCAGAUCCAGCCCAGCCAGCUGGAAUUGUUCUACUGUUUGUACGAGAUGCAGGAGGAGGACUUCGUGCAAAGGGCCAUGGACUAUUUCCCCAAGAUUGAGAUCAAUCUCUCCACCAGAAUGGACCACAUGGUUUCUUCCUUUUGCAUUGAGAACUGUCAUCGGGUGGAGUCACUGUCCCUGGGGUUUCUCCAUAACAUGCCCAAGGAGGAAGAGGAGGAGGAAAAGGAAGGCCGACACCUUGAUAUGGUGCAGUGUGUCCUCCCAAGCUCCUCUCAUGCUGCCUGUUCUCAUGGAUUGGUGAACAGCCACCUCACUUCCAGUUUUUGCCGGGGCCUCUUUUCAGUUCUGAGCACCAGCCAGAGUCUAACUGAAUUGGACCUCAGUGACAAUUCUCUGGGGGACCCAGGGAUGAGAGUGUUGUGUGAAACGCUCCAGCAUCCUGGCUGUAACAUUCGGAGAUUGUGGUUGGGGCGCUGUGGCCUCUCGCAUGAGUGCUGCUUCGACAUCUCCUUGGUCCUCAGCAGCAACCAGAAGCUGGUGGAGCUGGACCUGAGUGACAACGCCCUCGGUGACUUCGGAAUCAGACUUCUGUGUGUGGGACUGAAGCACCUGUUGUGCAAUCUGAAGAAGCUCUGGUUGGUCAGCUGCUGCCUCACAUCAGCAUGUUGUCAGGAUCUUGCAUCAGUAUUGAGCACCAGCCAUUCCCUGACCAGACUCUAUGUGGGGGAGAAUGCCUUGGGAGACUCAGGAGUCGCAAUUUUAUGUGAAAAAGCCAAGAAUCCACAGUGUAACCUGCAGAAACUGGGGU